CUUCGGCGCGGGACUUUCGGCGGGUCCCGGCCGGGCAGACCCAAGUGCCGGCGGCGGAGACUGCAGUGGAGCCAGUACCGGCUGUAGUGGCCGGGGCCGUGGCGGGAGAGUCAUGUCAGAGCCGCAGCCGCGGGGCGCAGAGCGCGAUCUCUACCGGGACACGUGGGUGCGAUACCUGGGCUAUGCCAAUGAGGUGGGCGAGGCUUUCCGCUCUCUUGUGCCAGCGGCGGUGGUGUGGCUGAGCUAUGGCGUGGCCAGCUCCUACGUGCUGGCGGAUGCCAUUGACAAAGGCAAGAAGGCUGGAGAGGUGCCCAGCCCUGAAGCAGGCCGCAGCGCCAGGGUGACUGUGGCUGUGGUGGACACCUUUGUAUGGCAGGCUCUAGCCUCUGUGGCCAUUCCGGGCUUCACCAUCAACCGCGUGUGUGCUGCCUCUCUCUAUGUCCUGGGCACUGCCACCCGCUGGCCCCUGGCUGUCCGCAAGUGGACCACCACCGCGCUUGGGCUGUUGACCAUCCCCAUCAUUAUCCACCCCAUUGACAGGUCGGUGGAUUUCCUCCUGGACUCCAGCCUGCGCAAGCUCUACCCAACAGUGGGGAAGCCCAGCUCCUCCUGAUCAUACUCUGGUACCUGGCCUGUGCAUCGGCCUCCUGCUUCAUGUCAACCUCCUACUCCUGCCAGGGAAUGUGGACACCUGGCUCCCUGGUGUCCAAAGACCCUGGCACCUGGGUGGGUUUGAGCUGGACAGAAGCUUAGAGACAAAGGCUUCAAGAAGCAGUGGCUGCAGGGAGUCACAGAAGGGCAGGACCUGAACGCUGUCUGCUUCCCUGGAAUCCAAGAUGCUGAGUGGAAGUGGACCCUGGGUGGGCCCGGCCCUGUCUUUUUCAGGAAAAUUACAUCCUCCCAUGGAGGAUGAGAGACUGAGGCUCAGGGAGGGCAAGGAAUAGGCCCAAGAUCACUUGGCAAGCUGGGCACCCAGGACCCCCAGGUGCUUGACAGAGUCACCCCAUGGUGGUAUGGCUGAACAAGGAGCGGCAGACAACUCAGGGAGAAACUCAGGAGUGCAGUACCAGGGACACCUCAGGACAGAUUCUCUGGCCAGGCCCUUCCCUGACCCAAUAAAUCCUGAAGAGGUU